GGCUUUGCUCAGAGCUUGUAGCGGCGCCACAAUCUCUGUCCUCUCAGGAACAGGAACUGGCUUGACGUCCUUUUCCUGCCCUAUCCAAGCCCCUGUUCUUGCAGCCCUUCUGAAGCUCAGCCUGGCACCGGCCCCGGCGCCCCAGCCCCUGGCCAAGCCUCUGCUGUCAUUUCUCCUCCCUCCUCUCAGUCUGCAGCUGCGGGACGGGCCGGGCUCCUCAGUUUCUGCUGUGUUGUGACCCCACGAGGCGCUCAGCACCCAGGGAAGGCGCGUGUGUCCCCGAUGCUGGCUCCUCCCUGAGCCCCGACGGCUCUCGAGGUUCUGAGCCUGUGGCCUGCACAGGGAACUUCCUCUCCGACUGCAUUUAUGCCUCUGUGGAUGUGAAGGCUAUUUCUAGAAAUCUCUUCCUUUGCAGAAACACCCGAAACCCUCCUGCCAGGAAGACCAGGGCCUGGGAAGAGGGUCGCUCUCCGGCCAUUCUCCCCUCACCCUCCUCACCUUCCUCACAUCCUGUGCCCUGGGGGACCAGCAGCUGCUUCCACCCAGAACAAGCGGGAGCCUGUGUCAGGAAAGCAUGUCAGAGCAGAGCUGCCAGAUGUCCGAACUGCGGCUCCUCCUCCUGGGAAAAUGCCGCUCGGGAAAAAGUGCCACAGGAAAUGCCAUUCUGGGCAAACAUGUGUUCAAGUCCAAGUUCAGUGAUCAGACAGUGAUCAAAAUGUGCCAGAGAGAGAGUUGGGUCCUGAGAGAAAGGAAGGUUGUGGUAAUUGACACCCCUGACCUUUUCUCCUCAAUAGCUUGUGCUGAAGACAAGCAACGCAACAUCCAACACUGCUUGGAGCUCUCUGCUCCCAGCCUCCAUGCUCUGCUCUUGGUAAUUGCCAUCGGCCAUUUCACAAGGGAGGAUGAGGAAACAGCCAAGGGCAUCCAACAAGUGUUUGGAGCUGAAGCCAGGAGGCACAUCAUUAUUGUCUUCACUCGGAAGGAUGAUUUGGGGGAUGACUUGCUGCAAGAUUUCAUUGAAAAAAACAAACCUCUCAAGCAGUUGGUUCAAGACUAUGAGGGCCGAUACUGCAUUUUCAACAACAAGACCAAUAGUAAGGAUGAGCAGAUCACCCAGGUGUUGGAGCUCCUUCGCAAGGUUGAGUCUUUGGUGAAUACGAACGGAGGACCCUAUCAUGUGAACUUCAAAACUGAAGGCAGCAGGUUUCAAGAUUGUGUGAAUGAAGCUGCAUCUCAAGAGGGAGACAAGCCACAGGGCCCAAGGGAAAGGCAGCUGCAGUCCACAGGACCCGAGCAGAAUCCGGGGACAUCAGAACUGACAGUCCUCCUUGUGGGGAAACGCGGUGCUGGAAAAAGUGCAGCAGGAAACAGCAUUCUGGGGAGGCAGGCCUUUCAGACCGGAUUUAGUGAGCAGUCAGUAACCCAGAGCUUCUUGUCUGAGAGCAGAAGCUGGAGAAAAAAGAAAGUUUCGAUCAUUGAUGCUCCGGACAUCUCAUCUUUAAAGAACAUUGACUCAGAAGUUAGAAAACACAUCUGUACAGGCCCCCAUGCCUUCCUGCUGGUGACACCACUGGGCUUUUACACUAAGAAUGAUGAGGCAGUGCUGAGCACCAUCCAAAACAAUUUUGGAGAAAAAUUCUUUGAGUACAUGAUCAUACUUCUUACCAGGAAAGAAGAUUUAGGGGAUCAGGAUCUAGAUACGUUCUUAAGAAACAGCAAUAAAGCUCUCUAUGGUCUCAUCCAGAAGUGUAAAAACAGAUAUAGUGCCUUCAACUACCGGGCAACAGGAGAAGAAGAGCAAAGGCAGGCGGACGAGCUCCUGGAAAAAAUUGAGAGCAUGGUGCAUCAGAAUGGGAACAAGCAUUGUGUUUUCAGAGAAAAAGAAACCCUGAACAUUGUCCUUGUGGGGAGAAGCGGGACUGGGAAGAGUGCGACCGGGAACUCUAUCCUGGGGAGCCUCGUCUUCACCUCUCGGCUCCGGGCCCAGCCAGUCACCAAGACCAGCCAGAGUGGCAGGAGGACAUGGGACGGACAGGAGGUGGUGGUUGUGGACACUCCUUCCUUCAACCAGAUGCUGGAUGUCGAAAAGGACCCAUCCCGGUUAGAAGAGGAGGUCAAGCGCUGUUUGUCCUGCUGUGAAAAAGGGGACACAUUUUUUGUCCUGGUGUUCCAGCUGGGACGAUUCACUGAAGAGGACAAAACAGCUGUGGCGAAACUGGAGGCCAUCUUUGGAGCAGACUUUACGAAAUACGCGAUUAUGCUGUUCACCCGGAAGGAAGACCUAGGGGCGGGGAAUUUGGAAGACUUCAUGAAGAACUCAGAUAACAAAGCCCUUCGGCGCAUUUUUAAAAAGUGUGGGCGGCGAGUUUGUGCUUUUAACAACAAAGAAACAGGCCAGGCCCAGGAAACCCAGGUGAAAGCUCUUUUAACAAAGGUCAAUGAUCUGAGAAAAGAAAGUGGGUGGUCCGGGUAUCCCCAUACACAGGAGAACGUCAGCAAACUAAUUAAAAAUGUCCAGGAAAUGUCCCAAGCCGAAAAACUCCUUAAAAAUUUAAUAGGUAUUUUACAAUAGGUAGCCGAAGUGCCUGGGGUCUCUUCAAUUAGAGACACCCUCAGGUUGGGGGGAGGGGCGGGGCAUGGUACAACCUGUGGGAAGGGAAGCGGGUUCAUGGCUUUGAGGGCCUGAGAGGCAAAUGCAUCCCGCCUUGUGAUGUAUCAGCUAUUUGUAGAUAAAUAAAUUGCAGGUGGGGGCGAAUAGUAGGGUAUUAUAAAGGAGAAAGAAGAUACAAGGUGGGGAAAUCUGGAAAAAGAUUUCAGACAUUAGGCUGAUAAUAAGUGGUAGAAUCAAGUCACAAGAAUCACCUCACUUGUGUAGGUAGGUUGGAAUCAGGAUAGACACUGUGAUCAAGGCUGAGGCCACCUGGGAUGAGAAUAUAGAUAGUCGUACAACAACCCAGGGGAUCCAGAUACAUGAGACCAGGGCAGCGUUCAGCACACUCCUGGGCAUGGCGGAAGCAGGAAGCAGACUCCAGAGGGCCUCCCUGUUGUCCAGGGCCGUUGGCUCCCUGAGCUCUCCUGUCUCCUUUGGGAUGCGACUUAGGGCUAGAGUGUUCUUUUCUUCACACGUUAGCCAUUCCUUACGGCUCUUCACGUUCCACGCCUAGAUGUGAAGUGGGACAUAGUCUUCCAUUGCUGGCUGUCCCUGAGGAAACAGACAUGAGUCUUGGAGGUUCUGAAUGAUUUUAUUGCUAAUUAUCACAGUGACAUAGACUAGAACAGAAAUUAGAAGCAUAGUAAGAUUGCCAAAAUCAGAGAAUCUUGCAAAGUUCUGUAAUUCUAAGUGUUGUUCUAGAUUUCCUCUAGAGAAGGUUAUUAGAAUCUCCAUUGCGUUUCUCUUUCUCCUUCUCUUUCCCUUGAGGUUAGGAAACAGGUUAAAACUCAGAGAACUCCAAUAAUAAUGGUUUAAAAACAUCAGGGGCUUCCUGUAUCUCCUGUCAGGAAGCCGAGGAAUAAGCAGGCUGGGGCUGGUGGGCGUCAACAUCCCAGUUUUGUUCUAUCUUUCUGUCCCACCUGCACUGGGAUGUGGCUUCUACACUCGAAUUUGCUUCUUGGUUUCAAGACAGUGGUGUUCUUUCCAUAGCUGAGCAGAUUAUUUUGAGAGGUGGGUGAUAUGUGAGAGAGAAAUCUGGAACCUUCUUCUGGGUAGAUACAGGAUAAGAUAGAUACAGGGUAAAAUGUUGAGCACUUUGUACAUGCUUUGAGAGCAUAAUCUUUGUCAUCUGUUUUUUUCCCCUAGACAAUAUCAGGUUACCGUCAACAUUAAUCCAUUUAAAAGGACAUGGACUGUUGCCAUUAAUACUUUUGGAUUCCAUAUAACCCUUAACACAAUAACUUCUAGAAAAUGUGUGUGCCGUAGACACAAAGAAGGGAACAAUAGACACCAGGGUAUACUUGAGGGUGGAGGGUGGCAGGAGGGUGAAGAUUGAAAAGCUGCCUAUUGCGUGUUAUGCUGGUUUCCUGGGUGACAAAAUUACCUGUACACCACACCCCUGUGACACACAACUUACUCAUGUAACAAACCUGUGCAUGUACCCCUUGAACCUGAAAUAAAAAUUGGAAAGUAAAAAAAAGUGUGUAAAUAUAUUUAGUUGAAUCAAAUAAUAAAGAUGAAUCAUUAUGAAUUCA